AUUCUCUUGGAGCAAGCAGGGAAGCAGAGGAGCAGCAGGGUCAGGGUGCUGGGUUCCUAAGGUGCAAGGAUGCAGAACAGAACUGGCCUCAUUCUCUGUGCUCUUGCCCUCCUGAUGGGUUUCCUGAUGGUCUGCCUGGGGGCCUUCUUCAUUUCCUGGGGCUCCAUAUUCGACUGUCAGGGGAGCCUGAUUGCGGCCUAUUUGCUUCUGCCUCUGGGGUUUGUGAUCCUUCUGAGUGGAAUUUUCUGGAGCAACUAUCGCCAGGUGACUGAAAGCAAAGGAGUGUUGAGGCACAUGCUCCGACAACACCUUGCUCAUGGGGCCCUGCCCGUGGCCACAGUAGACAGGCCAGACUUUUACCCUCCAGCUUAUGAAGAGAGCCUUGAGGUGGAAAAGCAGAGCUGUCCUGCAGAGAGAGAGGCCUCUGGCAUUCCUCCACCUCUAUAUACAGAGACGGGCCUGGAAUUCCAGGAUGGAAAUGACUCCCACCCAGAGGCCCCACCAUCUUAUAGAGAGUCCAUAGCCGGCCUGGUGGUGACAGCAAUCUCAGAGGACGCCCAGAGGCGAGGCCAAGAGUGCUGAGGCAGAGAAAGCUCUCCAGCACUCAUGAUGCCACCACUGUGGGGAGCAGCUACUGAUAAUAAAGGCAAACGAGGGACUGUGGGAGGAAAAGCCACACCAGGGACCCCACAAGAGAGCUUGGGGAGGGGAUGACAGCCCUGAAUUCCAGACAUAACUGGCCAUGCCAGGGCAGGGCAGGCCAGGGGCCCUGGAAGGGUGUGGCCAACACCAAGCAGACAUUUCAGAGCAUUCACACUAAUCUUAACCCCGGCUGGCCUUGGGUCCCCAAAGGUGUCACUCUGAGAGCUCUGCUUACAGAGAUUCUUUCUGCUGUCACUCAAUUUCCCUCCCAUCACCUCAACUCCAGCCAGGGAGGAAUAGAUGCUGGUUGUCAGGACAGCCACAUGCCUUCCUGUUCUAUAUCACCUAGUAAUCUCAAAGCGAAGGUUUGUUGUUUAAUUUAUUGAUUGUUCAGCCUUUUGUUUUGUUAGCUUGUUUCCUAGUUACCUCCAGCUGACCAUACUACCAGAGUGAGGCAGUACUUCACAUCCUGGGAGAUAUGCCCUCGGAACCCAUGAAUGUUAUUUUGUAUUAUUUUAUUUUCAUGAUAUGUAUUUUUUCUAUGUAAAAGGAAAAUGACUGUAAUAUUUGCCUUCAAGAUGGUUCAAACACAAAAUAUUAAAUGAGCUGUUUCUUAAAA